AGCACUCAUUGGACUUCAGCAUGACUACUCAGUUGCCAGCUUACGUGGCAAUUUUGCUUUUCUAUGUCUCAAGAGCCAGCUGCCAGGACACUUUCACUGCAGCUGUUUAUGAGCAUGCAGCGAUAUUGCCCAAUGCCACCCUAACACCAGUGUCUCGUGAGGAGGCUUUGGCAUUAAUGAAUCGGAAUCUGGACAUUUUGGAAGGAGCGAUCACAUCAGCAGCAGAUCAGGGUGCGCAUAUUAUUGUGACUCCAGAAGAUGCUAUUUAUGGCUGGAACUUCAACAGGGACUCUCUCUACCCAUAUUUGGAGGACAUCCCAGACCCUGAAGUAAACUGGAUCCCCUGUAAUAAUCGUAACAGAUUUGGCCAGACCCCAGUACAAGAAAGACUCAGCUGCCUGGCCAAGAACAACUCUAUCUAUGUUGUGGCAAAUAUUGGGGACAAGAAGCCAUGCGAUACCAGUGAUCCUCAGUGUCCCCCUGAUGGCCGUUACCAAUACAACACUGAUGUGGUAUUUGAUUCUCAAGGAAAACUGGUGGCACGCUACCAUAAGCAAAACCUUUUCAUGGGUGAAAAUCAAUUCAAUGUACCCAAGGAGCCUGAGAUUGUGACUUUCAAUACCACCUUUGGAAGUUUUGGCAUUUUCACAUGCUUUGAUAUACUCUUCCAUGAUCCUGCUGUUACCUUGGUGAAAGAUUUCCACGUGGACACCAUAGUAUUCCCAACAGCUUGGAUGAAUGUUUUGCCACAUUUGUCAGCUGUUGAAUUCCACUCAGCUUGGGCUAUGGGCAUGAGGGUCAAUUUCCUUGCAUCCAACAUACAUUACCCCUCAAAGAAAAUGACAGGAAGUGGCAUCUAUGCACCCAAUUCUUCAAGAGCAUUUCAUUAUGAUAUGAAGACAGAAGAGGGAAAACUCCUCCUCUCGCAACUGGAUUCCCACCCAUCCCAUUCUGCAGUGGUGAACUGGACUUCCUAUGCCAGCAGUAUAGAAGCGCUCUCAUCAGGAAACAAGGAAUUUAAAGGCACUGUCUUUUUCGAUGAAUUCACUUUUGUGAAGCUCACAGGAGUUGCAGGAAAUUAUACAGUUUGUCAGAAAGAUCUCUGCUGUCAUUUAAGCUACAAAAUGUCUGAGAACAUACCAAAUGAAGUGUACGCUCUAGGGGCAUUUGACGGACUGCACACUGUGGAAGGGCGCUAUUAUCUACAGAUUUGUACCCUGUUGAAAUGUAAAACGACUAAUUUAAACACUUGCGGUGACUCAGCUGAAACAGCUUCUACCAGGUUUGAAAUGUUCUCCCUCAGUGGCACUUUCGGAACCCAGUAUGUCUUUCCUGAGGUGUUGCUGAGUGAAAAUCAGCUUGCACCUGGAGAAUUUCAGGUGUCAACUGACGGACGCUUGUUUAGUCUGAAGCCAACAUCCGGACCUGUCUUAACAGUAACUCUGUUUGGGAGGUUGUAUGAGAAGGACUGGGCAUCAAAUGCUUCAUCAGGCCUCACAGCACAAGCAAGAAUAAUAAUGCUAAUAGUUAUAGCACCUAUUGUAUGCUCAUUAAGUUGGUAGAAUAUUGACUUUUUCUCUUUUUUAUUUGGGAUAAUUUAAAAAAUGAUGGAUGAGAAAAGAAAGAUUGGUCCGGGUUAAUAUUAUCCUCUAGUAUAAGUGAAUUACUAGUUUCUCUUUAUUUAGACAAACACACACACACCAGAUAAUAUAAACUUAAUAAAUUAUCUGUUAAUGUAGAUUUUAUUUAAAAAACUAUAUUUGAACAUUGGUCUUUCUUGGACGUGAGCUAAUUAUAUCAAAUAAGUAUCACAAAUCUUUUACGCAGAAGAAAUAAAAACUACGGGUAGAAAACAUAAGAACUAUCAUAAAAUUUACUUACAAGGAGGCUGCUCUUGUUACCACUUUUAUUAUAUUACGUAUCACUUAUUCAGCUCUGCUGAAAAUUUCCAAUGACUUUGUUUGUUUGCUCUUUUUGUUUUUUACCUAAACAAUACAUUUUGAUUCUCUUGUGGGUUGAUAAUGUCUCCCCAAAAUUUACAUGUUGAAGCACCUCAGAAUGUGACUGUAUUUGGAGACAGGGUCUUUAAAGAGGUAAAAUAAGGUCAUUAGGAUAGACCCUAAUUCAAUAUGACUGAUGAUCAUAAAAGAAGAGGCGAGUAGGGCACAACAGGCACAAAGGGAGACCAUAAGGAGACACAGAGGAAGGACAACUCUUUACAAGCUAAGAAGAGAGGGCCUCAGAAGAAACCAACCCUGCCAACACCUUGAUCUUGGACUUCCAGCCUCCAAAACUAUGAGAAAUAAAUUUCUAUUGUUUAAGUCACCCAGUCCAUGGUACUUUGUUAGGCAGCCCUGGCAAAUGAAUCAAAGACCCAUUCCUGUUCCUCUCCCCACCACUACUGUUUUCUACUGUAAUCUGAAGCUUCAACAAAAGGCUUACCUGGUAAGAAUAUUCAGCUGGUCUGGGUCCUCAAGACUCCAAUAGACACUCUUAGAGAAGGAUUGCUGAUGGAUUGAUAGUGAAACCAUUAGAUCAUUGAAUUCCUCUGGAAUUAGAAAACCAGAGAGUCCCAUUUUAAGAAAUUAGAUAUUUAAUAUAGCAUUGUGUGUUCUAUUUUAGUAACAGCAGAAUCUCUUGACAUUACACAACUCAGUGAAACAACAUCAUUUAAGCCAAAAUAUCUCCCAACUGACUGAUAGACUCUGAGCACUAAUAUCAUAGUGCUGUGAUGAUGGACAAUUACAUAGUACCGAUAACAGCCAUGCACUGUGCAAAGCAUGCCCUUCUGCACAGGAGAGCAAGGCACUUGCAGUAGUGAUCUAUGCCAGCAAAACAUCAUUUUGAGACAAACAUUUUUGUGGCAGAUGUUUUUCCUAAAAAGUACUAUAUCAUCCAAGAAAUAUUUGAGUAAAAUCCCUUGUUCUUUUGGGUGACAUUAACUGACAUUUGCUUUUUUUCAAGACCUAAUAGAAAAUAAGAAAGCCCAUAAUGUAUUUAGAAACAGGAAUCCUCAGAGCAAUUCUCUGUAUUCUCAUAUAAUUUCAAUGUAAAACAGAAAACAUAUUGAUGUGUUGGUGAUAGGCUUGAAUUAUUAAAAACUUCAAAAACAUCCUAAGUGUUUCUUUUUUGCUCAACGUUGUCAACUAUAGUAGGUCUCCCUUGUGGUGUAAUGAAUUGCCCCCAAACUAUUAUCUUAAAACAACAAACAUUUAUUAUCUUAUAGCAUUUCUGAGGGUCAGGAUCUGGGACUGGCUUAGUGGAGUUGUUCUGGAUCAGGGCCUUUGGAAAGUUGUAGUUAACUUGUCCCCAGGGCUGCCAUCAUCUCAAGGCUCGGGUGGGGCUGGAGAAAAUCUGCUUCUCAGCUCACUCACGGCGGUUGCCAGGCCUCCAUUCUUUAGGAUGCUAGAAAAACUUUCAUAAAAUGUCAUCUGGCUUCUCCUAGAGCAAUGAUACUGAGAGAGAAAGCACAUGAGAGAAAGAGCGAGGGAACUUGGAUGUAAGCCACAGUCUUUGAAAACCUAAUCACAGAAGUGACAUCUCUUCUUCCACAUGAUGUUGGUCACAUGGACCAACAAUGGCACAACGUGGACAGAAUCAAACAGAGUUGAGAAUAUCAGGAGGUGGGGCUUCAUGGGGGCCAUUUUGGAUGCUAUCAUAGUGAAUAUAUGUAUUUAUAUUUAUAUCUGUAUAUAUUGCAAUGUAAUUUAAAAAAUAGGAUUGUUUUCCUUUUCUUUUUGCUAUAUGUGAUAUGUAUUUCAAAAUACACUCCCAAUAGUUACGUCUGAAAAGCACUACACUAAAAAACUUUCUAUACAUUGAAUAAUUAAAUUAAAUAAUCUAAUAAUCUCUA